GGGCACCUUCUCCGAGGCGCGGUCGCGGCUCUGGGGUUCCUCCCAUGCAGUUGUCCCCGGGAGGGCCCGGGCGGGCGUGCAGUCCAGGCUCUCCCAUGCCCCGACCGUGGGCGUCGGGCACGGCACUUCCCUGUUGGGCCUCUGGCUUCUCUGCUUUUACCUUGAGGGUUAAUUUAUUCACCAGGAUUUAGAUGUCGGGGGCGGGGGAGGGUGGUUGGCGGCGGGAGUUGCUGAGAGGGCCGGCCGCUUAUCCCUGUUUGGUCCCACUUUUCUCCCAGCACCUGCCCUUGUUCACCGCCUCUUCAUCUACUUGGAUUUGGCUCGAAUAAACCCUCAGCUCCCGGCCAGCGCUGAGAGCCCUGGCGGAAGAGUGGGUAGCGGUGGCCUUAAGUAUUAAAUCUGUGGCGUCGGAGCCUGCUUCUUGGGGGAGAGACUCGUUGAAAAGGGAGUGUGUUGGGGAGGUGUUGUGCGCUGAGGGGAGUUAGAACUUCCCGGUCGGUUACCCAGUGGGAAGCUGCGGGGCACAAAGCCCAGAAUUUGCUGCUAAUCGCUGGGUGCCCUGGAGACAGAGGGGGCGUGUCCUCUGCGGAUUCCAUUCUCACCUUCCCCUCCCGCUUCUGAUCUCGCUGUUUGCUCCACCCUUGCUCCCCACCCACUAUCAGCUCCAGCGGGUGGGGGUGAAGGGCUGUCCCCAGGCCAACACCUCCUUCCAGGCUUUGGGGAGUGGGGAUUCUUUCCCCGGAUGGGCAGAGUUCCUUCUGCAGUGGCGCUACCGUCCGUGCUGCCCUCCUGGAAACACCGGGGUUUGGGGCAGGAACACUUCACCUGAAAGCAGGCCUGCUUGGCGCCUCCCGGCACAUCUGUGGUCUCCUCUGCACGUCGCUCGCGCAGCCUCCUUGCCUGGAAUGUCCUUCGCUGCCCAUCCUCAUAGGCCCACCUGGGAGAGAUCAUAUCCAUGCCCCCUGCCCCAGGUGUGGCAGGCGUGCUUGUGGGACACCCGUUUGACACGGUCAAGGGCAAGCUGUGAGUGGCAGGCACCAGACCAGCCUUGUGCUUGCUGGCAGCGCUACACGUGGCCGCUCUUCCCACUGAGCAAAGGCACAGCUGACGGCAAGGCAGGAUGCGCACCCUGAGCUGGGUUUGCGGGAGACUUCCAGUCUCCUUUUCUGGUGAGCCUAGGUGUGUGUUGGCAGAGACAGUGACUUACCAUAAGGGGUGGAUUGCAUCCAGCACAAGAGUGAGGGUCUGGCCUUUGCAUUGGCUGUGACCUUAAAAAGCUCUGUCCCUGGGCCUUGUGCAGGUCCGGGCCCCUCUGCCAGCCGGUUUUCUGCAUGACCUUGGGCAGGUCCCUGUAUCUUUGGGCUCAAACGUUGUCAUCGUGCCAGUGCUCAACAGCAUAAUUUAUGUUGGAUUAAAUGCUAGCUCUGAAAACCACAACUCUUCUAUCCACUGUAGGCCAAUUUGGGGAGGAGGCUGAAGGGCCAGGCUUUCUUGGCAGGCAGCGGCCCCACGUUUGCUGCACCGGCCUGCCGAGAGUGAGGCCGUGCAGAGCCUGCCCACACAGCCCCCGGCCCCAGCCAUGCCCACGCGCUGCCUAGCCAGGCCACCCGUGAAGCCUCCCCCAGGCCAGAGCAGCCCAGGACAGCCUGGCAGUGUCCACGUUGCACUGUGUUUAUGUCUCGUGGUCAUGUGUUGUGAACGCCUCUCGCAGCCAAGAAGUGCUUCACAUUCACUUCCUCUUUCCAGCUCCGUGGAGGCCUGGGCUCUCUGAGCUAUGAAUUGGCCAGACCUGCUGGGCUUCUGCCCGGCCCCCUCAGGCAGCCCCUGGCAGGCCUGGGAGCACUUUCGUUCUGGUGCUCUGCUGUCCUGAGCCACUGAGCCCGCGAGCAGCACCCCUGAAGUGACUCAGGGACAGGAGUUUCUCCAGCCCAUGAGAUUUUACUCCCCAGACCCUACUUCACUGGCGUCUGGAGGGUGGUCUUUGAGAAGAUCUAUAUGUGAUCCUUUUGUUUUGUUUUGUUUUUGUUUUUGCCACUCUGUCGCUCCAGCAGCAUCACAUCUGGACAUACCUACCUUAAAAAGCUGAACUUCUUUUCUUUGAGAUGGAGUCUGUGUCUGUCACUCAGUUUGGAGUGCAGUGGCGCGACCUUGGCUUACUGCAACUUCUUCCUCCUGGGUUCAAGUGAUUCUCCUGCCUCGGUUCCCCCCCCAACCCCCUGGGUAGCUGGGAUUACAGGCACGUGCCAGCACGCCUGGCUACUGUUUGUUUUUAGUUGAGGUCCAGCACAUAUAGAAAGUGCACACAUCCUGGCCAGGCUAGUGGCUCAUGCCUGUAAUCCCAGCACUUCUGGAGGCUGAGGCGGGCGGAUCACAAGGUCAGGAGAUCAAGACCAUCCUGGCUAACACGGUGAAACUCUGUCUCUACUAAACAUACAAAAAAUUAGCCGGGCGUGGUGGCGGGUGCCUGUAGUCCCAGCUACUCGGGAGGCUGAGGCAGGAGAAUGGCGUGAAUCCGGGAGGCGGAGCUUGCAGUGAGCCAAGAUCGCGUCACUGCACUCCAGCCUGGGCAACGGAAUGAGACUCCGUCUCAAAAAAGAAAAAAGAAGGAAAGUGCACACAUCCUAGGUGUACAAGUCGUCGCAAAACACAUGCGUGGCGAGCUGCCACCCAGGAGAAACAGAACAUGGCCAGCCCUCUGGAAGUCUUCCCUCCUGCUCCUAUCAACUCCUCCCUCCCCUUCUGAGGCUUCCACUGGCCUAACUUCCUCCUUUUUUUUUGAGACACGGUCUUGCUCUGUCACCCUAGGUGGAGUGCAGUGGUGCAAUCAUAGCCCACUGCAGCCUUGAUUUCCCAGGCUCAAGCAAUCCUCCCACCGCAGCCUCUCAAGUAGCUGAAACUACAGGCACACACCACCAUGCCUAGCUCAUGUUUUUUUUGAAGUUAUUAGUAGAGAUGGGGUCUUGAUAUGUUGCCCAGCUGGUCUCAAACUACUGGGCUCAAGUGAUCCUCCUGCCUUGGCCUCCCAAAGUGCUGGGAUGACAGGCCUGGCCCACUGUCCUCACUUCCAACACCACGGGUCCCUUUUGCCUGGUUGAAUAUAAUUGCAGCUGUACCCUAGGAUCAUCAGGGGCCACCCGAGUCUGUGUCAGUCCGUACUGUCACAUGGCCACAGACUAUCUCAUGGCUGGGACAGUCACAGUUUAUUCCCCCAGGCCCUUGGGACUGAAAGAAUCCAAGAUCUGGAUCUCCUCUAUAGCGCCCAGAACCACAGCCACCGUCCUGAAGCACACGGCCUUCACACGUUUCUACACGAAGGGAGUUUUCUGUCCUGCUUCCUUGGACACAGCAAUAAUCAGGGAGCAGUUGUCUUGACCUAUGAUGAGGGGGUGACCGGCCAUCCCUGGGCAUGGGAUGGGGAGUGUGGGUGGGGGCUGGCUGUGGGGGCUCCGCGCCUGGAUGUGAUGUUGAAAUUUUGUGUUGCUUUAACCGCCUUUACUUUCUGAGCUAGGGGCUGUCUCCAUCCAUAGCAAAAGUGUAACUUUGUUGUAGAUGGGCGUAAGCCUCACCCUGGAGAGCGCUAGUACGGCUUCAGGUCCAGAGCGUGGAGAAGCCUCAGUACCGCGGGACGUUGCACUGCUUCAAGUCCAUCAUCAAGCAAGAGAGCGUGCUGGGCCUGUACAAGGGCCUGGGCUCGCCGCUCAUGGGGCUCACCUUCAUCAACGCGCUGGUGUUCGGGGUGCAGGGCAACACCCUCCGGGCCCUGGGCCACGACUCGCCCCUCAACCAGUUCCUGGCAGGUGCGGCGGCGGGCGCCAUCCAGUGCGUCAUCUGCUGCCCCAUGGAGCUGGCCAAGACGCGGCUGCAGCUGCAGGACGCGGGCCCAGCGCGCACCUACAAGGGCUCGCUGGACUGCCUCGCGCAGAUCUACGGGCACGAGGGUCUGCGUGGCGUCAACCGGGGCAUGGUGUCCACGUUGCUGCGUGAGACGCCCAGCUUCGGCGUCUACUUCCUCACCUAUGACGCUCUCACGCGGGCGCUGGGCUGCGAGCCGGGCGACCGCCUGCUGGUGCCCAAGCUGCUGUUGGCGGGCGGUACGUCAGGCAUCGUGUCCUGGCUCUCUACCUAUCCUGUGGACGUGGUCAAGUCGCGGCUGCAGGCGGACGGACUGCGGGGCGCCCCGCGCUACCGCGGCAUCCUGGACUGCGUGCACCAGAGCUACCGCGCCGAGGGCUGGCGCGUCUUCACACGGGGGCUGGCGUCCACGCUGCUGCGCGCCUUCCCCGUCAACGCUGCCACCUUCGCCACCGUCACGGUGGUGCUCACCUACGCGCGCGGCGAGGAGGCCGGGCCCGAGGGCGAGGCUGUGCCCGCCGCCCCUGCGGGGCCUGCCCUGGCGCAGCCCUCCAGCCUGUGACGCUCACCCCGCCCUCCUUCCCCAGGGCUCCUUCUCAGAAACCUGGGACAUAAAUUGGCCCCUGAGUCGAUUGCCCUGCUUCCUGCUGGGAUGCUGCGAGCUGUGGAGUCUAUCAGACGUGGGCUGAAUUUUGCUGAUCAGCUGGGUAGUUUUGGCCGAGAACUGCACUUGCCUCAGUGUUCUCAUCUAUGAAAUAAGGACCCUCAUGCCCACACUGUAGAGUCACGAAGCUCAGAGAUUAUUCCCAGCAGCAGCCAGCACCUGGCCUGGCUGAGGCCAUUGCACCGUUAUCCUGGAAACUGAGGCAGACACUCCAGCCCCUUUCUGGGAUCCUGGCCACGUCAUUGUGCUCCUGCCCUGCAGGCUGGCUCCCGGGGGUCUCUGAUGGCCAACCAAGGGGCCACCCAGGGACCUCUAACUCCACACAUCCUCCACCCGGGGGGGUGGUGGGCCACCCCUCUGGUCUGUGUUAGGGACAGAGGAAAACUUGGUGUGCCUCCUGGUGUCACAGAACUGGAUCCUCUGCAUACCCCAGCUUCUCCACAUGCCACUGCUAGGGGUACCCCAGCUGCUGCCACUCCUGCUGGAGGGUGAACUGGGGACCCUGCACCCUCCGGGAAGCCAUGGAGUCUGCUGGAGGCACCAUAUCAGCCUGCGGGACUAGGGUGGGGAGCAAACAGGCCAGCGGUGGAGGUCUGGACAGUUCAAGUGUGAUGCAGCUGUGGCAAGGAGAAAUCCUUCCGCCUCUGGGCCUCAGGCUGCCUGUCCAUAAAAUGGGGACAUGGCCAGCUGACGGACAACUGAGUCUCCGGCCCACCUACCACCGCCAGCCAGGAUCCCCCAAAGUGUGCAGAGGGCUCAGCAGAGAACAGUAUGGGACCCCCUCACCAGGCCUGGAACACCUCCAGCCACAAAGAAGCCAAAGGUCAGUCCCUCUGCUCCCCAGCAAACGGUGCCUCCCAGGCAUUCUCAGUGCCAGGGCUUCAUCCCUGUGAAGGCACAGGGCCUGCUAGUGGGCACAGGGGUGGCUAGUUGGGGCCUGGGGCAGAGGAGGGCUGCACCAGGCGUCCUGGGGAAUGUGCUCAGUGAAGACGACACUGGGCUUUGCACAGCCUGGUGUCGCUGUACAGAAACUGUCAAGGGAAUAAAGUGUUCUUUGUUUUUUAA